AGUUGGAGAGGAGGACUUCAGGCGGGUGGGACAAGAGAAACUGAAUCUGAGGUCCUUGGGGAGAAGCAGGCCCUGGAGUCCUGGGCAGCAGAUGCCAGGCUCUGAGCCCCAUGACUGCUGACCCUCCUCCCCUCCCUCUCAUCCUCAGCCCAGGGCUGCCAAAUUUAGCAAAGUGCCAUUCCAGCUGCAAUGCUUCCAAGCCGCCUCAGAUCAUCAAAACUUCACAUGCCCUGGGGAGCACUCAAGGAAAUUACCUUCUAGCACCAAUUUCCUAUGCGCGCUGAUUACUCAAACCUGGCCAGGGAGGCCUGGCCUCCAGUGUUUGGCAUCUGGGACUCAGGAGCCCUUAAGACAAGCUGAUGACAUCUUGCUGCCAGGGUCCCUUACCAUUAGAAAAGGGAACCAAAAAAUAGAAGUUAUAGAGUGAAAGUGUCCCCAGGCCAAAAGCCCAGGGCUCCAGGCUGCCAUCAGGAUGGUGGGUGAAGGACCCUACCUUAUCUCAGAUCUGGACCAGCGAGGCCGGCGGAGAUCCUUUGCAGAAAGAUAUGACCCCAGCCUGAAGACCAUGAUCCCAGUGCGACCCUGUGCAAGGUUAGCACCCAACCCGGUGGAUGAUGCCGGGCUACUCUCCUUCGCCACAUUUUCCUGGCUCACGCCGGUGAUGGUGAAAGGCUACCGGCAAAGGCUGACCGUAGACACCCUGCCCCCAUUGUCGACAUAUGACUCAUCUGACACCAAUGCCAAAAGAUUUCGAGUCCUUUGGGAUGAAGAGGUAGCAAGGGUGGGUCCUGAGAAGGCCUCUCUGAGCCACGUGGUGUGGAAAUUCCAGAGGACACGCGUGUUGAUGGACAUCGUGGCCAACAUCCUGUGCAUCAUCAUGGCAGCCAUAGGGCCGACAGUUCUCAUUCACCAAAUCCUCCAGCAGACUGAGAGGACCUCUGGGAAAGUCUGGGUUGGCAUUGGACUGUGCAUAGCCCUUUUUGCCACCGAGUUUACCAAAGUCUUCUUUUGGGCCCUUGCCUGGGCCAUCAACUACCGCACGGCCAUCCGGUUGAAGGUGGCGCUCUCCACCUUGGUUUUUGAAAACCUAGUGUCCUUCAAGACAUUGACCCACAUCUCUGUUGGCGAGGUGCUCAAUAUACUGUCAAGUGAUAGCUAUUCUUUGUUUGAAGCUGCCUUGUUUUGUCCUUUGCCAGCCACCAUCCCGAUCCUAAUGGUCUUUUGUGCGGCGUACGCCUUUUUCAUUCUGGGGCCCACAGCUCUCAUCGGGAUAUCAGUGUAUGUCAUAUUCAUACCCGUCCAGAUGUUUAUGGCCAAGCUCAAUUCAGCUUUCCGAAGGUCAGCAAUUUUGGUGACAGACAAGCGAGUUCAGACAAUGAAUGAGUUUCUGACCUGCAUCAGGCUGAUCAAAAUGUAUGCCUGGGAGAAAUCUUUUACCAACACUAUCCAAGAUAUAAGAAGGAGGGAAAGAAAAUUACUGGAAAAAGCUGGAUUUGUCCAAAGUGGAAACUCUGCCCUGGCCCCCAUCGUGUCCACCAUAGCCAUCGUGCUGACAUUAUCCUGCCACAUCCUCCUGAGACGCAAACUCACCGCACCCGUGGCAUUUAGUGUGAUUGCCAUGUUUAAUGUAAUGAAGUUUUCCAUUGCAAUCUUGCCCUUCUCCAUCAAAGCAAUGGCUGAAGCGAAUGUCUCUCUAAGGAGAAUGAAGAAAAUUCUCAUAGAUAAAAGCCCCCCAUCUUACAUCACCCAACCAGAAGACCCAGAUACUGUCUUGCUUUUAGCAAAUGCCACCUUGACAUGGGAGCAUGAAGCCAGCAGGAAAAGUACCCCAAAGAAAUUGCAGAACCAGAAAAGGCAUUUAUGCAAGAAACAGAGGUCAGAGGCAUACAGUGAGAGGAGUCCACCAGCCAAGGGAGCCACUGGCCCAGAGGAGCAAAGUGACAGCCUCAAAUCGGUUCUGCACAGCAUAAGCUUUGUGGUGAGAAAGGGGAAGAUCUUGGGAAUAUGUGGGAAUGUGGGAAGUGGAAAGAGCUCCCUCCUUGCAGCUCUCCUAGGACAGAUGCAGCUGCAGAAAGGGGUGGUGGCAGUCAAUGGAACUUUGGCCUACGUUUCACAGCAGGCAUGGAUCUUUCAUGGAAAUGUGAGAGAAAACAUACUCUUUGGAGAAAAGUAUGAUCACCAAAGGUAUCAGCACACAGUCCGCGUCUGUGGCCUCCAGAAGGACCUGAGCAACCUCCCCUAUGGAGACCUGACUGAGAUUGGGGAGCGGGGCCUCAACCUCUCUGGGGGGCAGAGGCAGAGGAUUAGCCUGGCCCGCGCUGUCUACUCCGACCGUCAGCUCUACCUGCUGGACGACCCCCUGUCGGCCGUGGACGCCCACGUGGGGAAGCACGUCUUUGAGGAGUGCAUUAAGAAGACGCUCAGGGGAAAGACAGUCGUCCUGGUGACCCACCAGCUACAGUUCUUAGAGUCUUGUGAUGAAGUUAUUUUAUUAGAAGAUGGAGAGAUUUGUGAAAAGGGAACCCACAAGGAGUUAAUGGAGGAGAGAGGGCGCUAUGCAAAACUGAUUCACAACCUGCGAGGAUUGCAGUUCAAGGAUCCUGAACACCUUUACAAUGCAGCAAUGGUGGAAGCCUUCAAGGAGAGCCCUGCUGAGAGAGAGGAAGAUGCUGGUAUAAUCGUUUUGGCUCCAGGAAAUGAGAAAGAUGAAGGAAAAGAAUCUGAAACAGGCUCAGAAUUUGUAGACACAAAAGUUCCUGAGCACCAGCUCAUCCAGACUGAAUCCCCCCAGGAAGGAACCGUGACCUGGAAAACAUAUCACACGUACAUUAAGGCUUCUGGAGGGUACCUCCUUUCUCUCUUCACUGUGUUCCUCUUCCUCCUGAUGAUUGGCAGCGCUGCCUUCAGCAACUGGUGGCUGGGUCUCUGGUUGGACAAGGGCUCACGGAUGACCUGUGGGCCCCAGGGCAACAGGACCAUGUGUGAGGUCGGCGCGGUGCUGGCAGACAUCGGUCAGCAUGUGUACCAGUGGGUGUACACUGCAAGCAUGGUGUUCAUGCUGGUGUUUGGCGUCACCAAAGGCUUCGUCUUCACCAAGACCACACUGAUGGCAUCCUCCUCUCUGCAUGACACGGUGUUUGAUAAGAUCUUAAAGAGCCCAAUGAGUUUCUUUGACACGACUCCCACUGGCAGGCUAAUGAACCGUUUUUCCAAGGAUAUGGACGAGCUGGAUGUGAGGCUGCCGUUUCACGCAGAGAACUUUCUGCAGCAGUUUUUUAUGGUGGUGUUUAUUCUCGUGAUCUUGGCUGCUGUGUUUCCUGCUGUCCUUUUAGUCGUGGCCAGCCUUGCUGUAGGCUUCUUCAUUCUGUUACGCAUUUUCCACAGAGGAGUCCAGGAGCUCAAGAAGGUGGAGAAUGUCAGCCGGUCACCCUGGUUCACCCACAUCACCUCCUCCAUGCAGGGCCUGGGCAUCAUUCACGCCUAUGGCAAGAAGGAGAGCUGCAUCACCUAUCACCUCCUCUACUUUAACUGUGCUCUCAGGUGGUUUGCGCUGAGAAUGGAUGUCCUCAUGAACAUCCUUACCUUCACUGUGGCCUUGUUGGUGACCCUGAGUUUCUCCUCCAUCAGUACUUCAUCCAAAGGCCUGUCAUUGUCAUACAUCAUCCAGCUGAGCGGACUGCUCCAAGUGUGUGUGCGAACGGGAACAGAGACGCAAGCCAAAUUCACCUCCGUGGAGCUGCUCAGGGAAUACAUUUCGACCUGUGUUCCUGAAUGCACUCAUCCCCUCAAAGUGGGGACCUGUCCCAAGGACUGGCCCAGCCGUGGGGAGAUCACCUUCAGAGACUAUCAGAUGAGAUACAGAGACAACACCCCCCUUGUUCUCGACAGCCUGAACUUGAACAUACAAAGUGGGCAGACAGUCGGGAUUGUUGGAAGAACAGGUUCCGGAAAGUCAUCGUUAGGAAUGGCUUUGUUUCGUCUGGUGGAGCCAGCCAGUGGCACAAUCUUUAUUGAUGAGGUGGAUAUCUGCAUUCUCAGCUUGGAAGACCUCAGAACCAAGCUGACUGUGAUCCCACAGGAUCCUGUCCUGUUUGUAGGUACAGUAAGGUACAACUUGGAUCCCUUUGAGAGUCACACCGAUGAGAUGCUCUGGCAGGUUCUGGAGAGAACAUUCAUGAGAGACACAAUAAUGAAACUCCCAGAAAAAUUACAGGCAGAAGUCACAGAAAAUGGAGAAAACUUCUCAGUAGGGGAACGUCAGCUGCUUUGUGUGGCCCGAGCUCUUCUCCGUAAUUCAAAGAUCAUUCUCCUUGAUGAAGCCACCGCCUCUAUGGACUCCAAGACUGACACCCUGGUUCAGAACACCAUCAAAGAUGCCUUCAAGGGCUGCACUGUGCUGACCAUCGCCCACCGCCUCAACACAGUUCUCAACUGCGAUCACGUCCUGGUUAUGGAAAAUGGGAAGGUGAUUGAGUUUGACAAGCCUGAAGUCCUUGCAGAGAAGCCAGAUUCUGCAUUUGCGAUGUUACUAGCAGCAGAAGUCAGAUUGUAGAGGUCCUGGCGGCUGAUUCUAGAGGAGGAAGAGGCUCUGUGAGAUGAAUAGGAGGAGUCUUCAGGAGGAGGGGCUGUCCUCUCCGCAGGCAGCCCUGGUCUUCAGCCCCUCCCAUCCACGGAGUGAGCUGGGGCUGAAGUUGUCCCCACUGCCAUACUCAGUCCAUGUCACCCCACUUGGUGGGCUUGGGGUUGGUUCUGGGUGGUGAACCGGGGCAGACCCAGCUAAUGGAUUAAAAAACUGCCCUUCACCUCCCAAAUCCCCAAGGGUUCCUCAUGUGUUUUCACCAAAACCACCCCAGUGCCUGAGAUUGAAAAUAUUGUAACUUUCAGUUAGAAAUCAGCCACAAUAAACAACAUGGGAAAAUGCCUUAGGAUGGAGUUUGCAAGGUUUCCUUGCCCAUUAUCAGAAGGAAAAAGAGCAGAAUUUUCUUCUCGUUUAACCCCACUCACUUCCAUCUUGACUGGGUGACAAGUGGUAAUGACACAGAUUUGUAGCGUGAAAGACUGAAUACAGUGUUUGGCCAAAAAUUUUUUUAAAAAUCAUAUUAUAUGUUUCAAUUGAUCUGUUAGAAUAACCAAGAAAACAAAAUGCUGGAGUUUCUCUAUAAAUGACACUUUUAUAUCUUCUUUAUUCGUCGUUAAAACGCGGUAGGAAAUUACCCUGAAAUGUCGCCUUGCAAUUAUUUCACUGAAGAUAUUCCAAUUUCCAUACUAUUUCCUCCAAUAGACCCUUGUUGCCUUCUCCCUUCACUCAGUAAUGAACCUUCACAGUCGCUUACCAAACAAAAAGCUUUCUCUCCAACCUGGAGGCUGGUUCUGAUGGAAGCAGUAAAGAUGUAUUCCCAGCAGCCCCAGGAGUGAGCGCUGCUAACUCAUGGUGACAUUUGGGAAAAAAAUAUUUAUAGAAAAUCCAGCAAGCUCUUGUGUAGUAGCCGCCAAGGGGCACGCUGGGAGUUCUGGCUGUUUUUCAUUCAUCAGGAAUGAAGGCCCCAUGAGGUUCCCUGGGCCUGCUUUCCAGGCCCCAGGCUGAGCUCUAAAUGUAGCUCAGGGCAGUGUGGUCAGCAAAGCUUCCAGACCACAACCCCCCACCCCACUUCCCUUGUAAGUGUUGGUCACGUACUUGCUUCCCCAGACGUGGAGGAAGGAGUGCCUGGCACCUGGAAGCACUCGGGAAACACUUGUGGCAGCCAUGAAUGACAGCAUCUAAUGAACUCGCUGAAACACAGCUGUGGAGCCUGGCGGACACCCCUCCCAGGUGUGUGUGCAUGUUAAGAGCUUAAUCUGGAUUUCUGGCCAAAAAGCCAACAGCCAGCAAUUCAAGGGCUGGGCAUGUGAGGUUAACCUCCAACCGAUUAUUCUCCAGCCCUCCUCCGGCCAGGCCUGGGCAGGGGUCUACCCAACCAGCGGGGAGGUGAGCACACCUGGCCUUAGGUAGAGCUUAUAACCUGGCAACUGCAUGAAAGCCCUGGCCCAGCAGCUUGGCAGCAAUGGAUCCUGCCCUCAGCAGAGGGUGCACUAAGACAUGUGGCUGAGAAGGACGUGAGCCAGGGGGUUCCUUCUGUGGGCAGCUCCAGGCCAAGUGUGGAUCUCUCUGUGAAGGGACACAGUGUAUCUUUGCCUGAUCUGAGCUUUCCCCCAUGGUGCAUGACCCUGACUGAAGGUCAUUAAACCCACAUCCACAGCGUUCUGAGCAGCUGCUCCCAGCUGAGUGUGGGCAUCACCUUUAUGGACAUAAGAUAACUUCCCCAAUAUGACAAGCAGACUGGGCAGUCUGUGCUGGCCAUGGGAAUCCAUGACAGUUGUGCAAUGUCAGGGAGGGAUGCUUUACUUUCUACCAACUGGACACCAGCCAGAUAAUCAGUCUGUGAUUUCAAGAGGUGGUGUUUUCAUGAGGACAGAGGAUAGACUACAAUGAUCCCUGCUGCUCCUUCAGAUGCAUUGAGAGAUGAAUCACCUCCUAUGACUCCUUUUCUGCCCACACUCGCUUUGGUUUACUCUGGCAGAAGAAGAACACCGACAUUGAUCCUGAUGUCUACUGAGACCUUGCAGUGUGCCAGGACUGUGACAAGCAUUUUUUCCAUGAAUUAUUUCACUGAAUCCUCAUCUCACCCCAUGAGAUGGGAUUUGAGGCUCACUGAGGUUAGUAACUUAUCUACAGAUGCCCAGGAAGGAAGGGACAGAGAUAGGGCUUGAACCCUAACCAGUCUGGCUCCACAGGCCCUGCUCCCAACCCCUUCACAACAAAGCCCCUCCAGUCCUUUCCCCUUGGCCUGUUGCAAGGACAGUGAUGGUCAUCAGUAUCAUCCCUGGGGGAGAGUGACUUCUGAGGGUUUGGCUGUUUGCAUGUAUAAGACACGAAACCAUCUUAGCAAACCCCUCUCCCACCCCAACCCCUUGCUAUCACUGCCAUGUCAGCCAAGGGGAGACUAUGUAGAAUAAUAGUAGCCAUUUAGCCAAAUUCCUCAAAGCACAGGCUUAGGUUAUUAAAUCCUGAACAUAUCCCUGUGGGGUAGGUGUCUGCUAUGAUCUGAACAUUGUGUUCCCCCAAAAUCCUCCUGUUGAAACAUAAUCCUCAGUGUGACAGUAUAGAGGUAGGGCCUUUAGGAGGUGAUUAAUUAGGUCAUGAGGGUGGAGACCUCAUGAAUAGGAUUGGCUCUCUUAUAAAAGAGACUUGGGGAAGCUUGUUCACCCCUUCCUCCAUGUGAGGACACAUAGAAGGCAUCAUCUGUGAGGAAUGGGCCCUCACUCAACACCAAAUCUGUUGGCACCUCGACCAUGGAUUUCCCAGCGUCCAGAACUGUGAGCAAUAAAUUUCUGUUGUUUAUAAAUUA